CUCUUCUCUCAUUGGCACUGCCUGUCUACUGCCGAGGGCAUUUGAGUGUGGGACCCAUGCCCUGCAUUUCUUCGCUACCCCACAGCUUCUGCUCAUGAAUCCAGCUCAAAUGUCAGAAGAAUUGACGUUAGUUUGAGAGACCAAACUAAGUUACAGCCUCUUUGGUUUCUGUUACUCUGGCUGGUCUUGAACUCCUGGACUCAAGUGAUCCAACCACCUCUGCUUCUCAAAGUGCUAGGACUACAGGUGUGUGCCACCGUGCCCAGCACACUUGGGGAGUUUUAAAAACUACUGAUGCCUGAGCACCACCCUCAGUGAUUCUGAUUUAAUUGUUGGGUGCAACGUGGACAUAAGAAUAUGCAGCCAAAUUUGAAAACACUGCUCUAAAAGCAGAGGGAGAUAUAGAACAGAGAGCACAGGGAUAUUUCCGGGGUAUAAUAAACAGGACUUGGUGGUUAGUUAUGAAUUGGAAGGGACAAAAAGAAUGGGGCCUGGGAACAAUCCUAGGUUUCUGGCUUGUGUCUGGGUGAAUGAAAGAAGCAUGCUUUGAGGAAAGAACAAACUACAUCUUGGACAGCCUGAAUCUGAGGUGCCUCUAGGAAUUCAAGUUGGGGAUGUUCAAUAGGUAUUUGUUUUUUAAUAGAUUUAUUUGGCCUAGUGAAGAAUAGAAAGUCCUUCUAAUUUUUAGGAAGACAAGAAAGCCAGAAGCAGCAUCUCUGGAAAAUAUUACCGUUGUACAGAGUGUAAGACCAUUUUCAUUCCGCACAGCUUCUUUAUUCAAAAUCCCCUUUCAAGCCAGUGCCCCAUCUGUGCUGAAAUGUUGUUUAACAUGUUGAUCUAUUUUCUUUUCUUUUUUUUUUUUUUUUUUUUUUGAGACGGAGUCUCGCUCUGUCGCCCAGGCUGGAGUGCAGUGGCGAGAUCUCUGCUCACUACAAGCUCCGCCGCCCGGGUUCACGCCAUCCUCCUGCCUCAGCCUCCCGAGUAGCUGGGACUACAGGCGCCCGCCACCACGCCCAGCUAAUUUUUUGUAUUUUUAGUAGAGACGGGGUUUCACUAUGUUAGCCAGGAUGGUCUCGAUCUCCUGACCUCGUGAUCCGCCCGCCUCGGCCUCCCAAAGUGCUAGGAUUACAGGCGUGAGCCACCAAUUCCGGCCAACAUAUUGAUAUAUUUUCAAGAAGGAUAUUAUAUAUGGGUACUUAACUUACUAUUCUUGUGCUAUCUGUAGGCUUAAAGCAUCCCAUAUGUAAAGUCGCUGGCAGCCUUCAAGUAGCAUUUAAAGGUAUAACAGCUUUAAAACUUCCCAUAAAUGAAAAUAAACAUACCCAUAAUUACUUCCUUUAAGAUUCGAGGCCAAAGACACUUAAACCUAAACUGCCUAGCUUGUUCAAUUUUCUAAUUGGUAAACAUUUACUGGGUUACCAAAGAUACCAAGUACAUUCGGAAAGACCAUGGCUCCUUGGUUUGUUUCUAAUUUAAAUUACACAGACACACUAAACAAGGACUGGGAGAGUGAUAUAUUUAGUUAAGUAACAGAUGGCAAAUGGACAUUCUGUCCAGCCUCUAUCACAUUCGUUUCUCAGUAUUCUAUGUUAGAGUGAUCUAAAUCUUGAAGAGAAUAAACCAGGAGGAAAUGCACCAGGCCCAGACGGAAUUUGUUUAUUCAACUAAGAAUACCAAGACUAGUGUAGAUUGAAACAUUCAAAGGGGAUAUGACUGGCUGAAAAGAUAUGAGACGAAGGAACAAAUAAAGCUGGAUUAAAGUAAUUAGGAAUGUAUUAGAGAUGAAAUAGGAAUUCUGAUUACUUGACUGCAAAAUAGUAAAAAAAAAAUGAAAUAAAAGAGAUGAAUGGAAGAUACUCUCCAAACCCUCACGUAGGCUUGCUAUUGUGGCUAAGUACUGUUCCUAACAGCCUCUGCAAAGACAGGUGCACUAAGAGGGCGGCUGCAGACGCACAGGGUGCUGCCGUCCUCUGGGAAAGGACAUUUCCUCGCCGAGAGCUGCAACAUCCCGGCACUUCUCUCCCUCGGCCUGCCAAUCUAGCAGGUGAACCCUGAGAACACAAAGGAAUGAAUAAUGCCGGGCAAACUGCCAAGAGCCAGAGUCGCCGAGUCUGGCAACUCCCUUCAACCGGGCGCAGCUCCAGCCACCCCGACCUGUCCUUGGAGGAGACGCUCUCUGGGCCACGGAGAACCGGCCAGGGAGACACCGGCCCCACUGCCCGGCGCGCUCGAGGCGAAGUCCCCUCCGCCAGGGACAGGCGUGGGGGCCGCAGUCGGGGCCACCCGGGUGCAGCGGGGCGGCUCCUGCGCGGGCGCGGAACGAACGUGCGCAAGGGAACAGCCGCGUCCAGAGCCGCCCGCAGCGGGCCCGGUGGGCGUGACGCCAUGACGCACAGCACGCGGGCGGCGCGCUGGGGCGGGGCGGCCGGGGGCGGGAGGAAGAAGUGGGAGGAGGAGGAGGGGAAAGCGGGGGCUGCGGGAGGGGGAGGUGGUAGUUGCGGCGCUGGUUCCCGGGAGCAGCCGUCGAGCCACAACUGCGGAGGAGGAGUUCGGGAAAGCGGCCGUCGGGACUCCUCCCCUCCGUCGUCUCCGCCCCGGUUGAGAGGCGCCUCGGCGCAUCGGAGGGACCCUCCCCCGCGCUUCCUCAGGCUGCUGUCGCCGCUGCUGGGAGAUGGGCCUACUCGCCCGCCACCCUGCGCUGCCGCCGCUCUGAGGAGUUAAAGGUACGGGCGGGCACCCGGAGGAGCUUGCGCCCCGGAGCGGGAGAGAAGGGGCGGCUCUCGCUUACGACCCAGGGAGCUCUGGCCGGGCCGCAGCCCUAGCGCCCCUGCCCGGGACAGAAAUGGAUUCGGAAGUCCGGUGGGAAAGGCGUCUCCUCCAGUGUCCAGCGUGGGCUCGGGGCCGUGGCCGGCUUAGGGGGUCAGGCCUCGGUCAGCUCCGGGUCCCCUACCCGGCCCAGGCGCGGGCGUCUCCCGGGCCGCGGGGGCCGAGGUGGAGCGUGGGAUCCGCCCCAAGCCCUGUCCUCCUGGUGCCUGUGCGGCCGGCGGCCGGCCCGGCGAUAUUAUGACGGGCCGAGGCGGCGCUCCCCUCGAGCUGUCUCCUGCCCCUAAAGCGGGGGAGACCCAAGGGCGGUUGCCGCGGGGAGGCGGCGGGGGCGGAACGCAUUCCUGACGGGUGAAAUCGGCUCUAACGGGACCGAUUUCCGGGCCUCGCUGCAAAUUUGGAGCCGGGACAUCGCCCCGCAAGCCGUGCUGCCUGGGGCCUUAGGGAGGGGAGCUGUGUUCGGAGGAAGAACAUCCAUGAUAGCAGUCUUCUGUAAAUCGAACUUUUCAAGAAUUCUCUGAAGGAACCAAGUAGGAUAUUCUUACAUCAUGACUUAAUGUGAAUGCAAGAACAAGAAAUAGGUUUUAUCUCUAAAUAUAAUGAAGGGCUGUGUGUAAACACUGACCCUGUCUCAAUUCUAACAAGCAUUUUAGACAUGAGUUUACAUCGGCAAAUGGGUUCAGAUCGAGAUCUUCAGUCCUCUGCUUCAUCUGUGAGCUUGCCUUCAGUCAAAAAGGCACCCAAAAAAAGAAGAAUUUCAAUAGGCUCCCUGUUUCGGAGGAAAAAAGAUAACAAACGUAAAUCAAGGGAGCUAAAUGGCGGGGUGGAUGGAAUUGCAAGUAUUGAAAGUAUACAUUCUGAAAUGUGUACUGAUAAGAACUCCAUUUUCUCUACAAAUACCUCUUCUGACAAUGGAUUAACUUCCAUCAGCAAACAAAUUGGAGACUUCAUAGAGUGCCCUUUGUGCCUUUUGCGGCAUUCUAAAGACAGAUUUCCUGAUAUAAUGACUUGUCAUCACAGAUCUUGUGUGGAUUGCUUACGACAAUAUUUAAGGAUAGAAAUCUCUGAAAGCAGAGUUAAUAUUAGUUGCCCAGAAUGUACUGAACGGUUUAAUCCCCAUGAUAUUCGCUUGAUAUUAAGUGAUGAUGUCUUGAUGGAAAAAUACGAAGAAUUUAUGCUUAGACGGUGGCUUGUUGCAGAUCCUGAUUGUAGGUGGUGUCCAGCUCCAGACUGUGGAUAUGCUGUGAUAGCAUUUGGAUGUGCCAGCUGUCCAAAAUUAACUUGUGGGCGAGAGGGCUGUGGAACAGAGUUUUGCUACCACUGUAAACAGAUUUGGCACCCCAACCAGACCUGUGAUGCUGCUCGACAAGAGAGAGCCCAGAGCUUACGUUUGAGAACUAUACGUUCUUCAUCCAUUAGUUAUAGUCAAGAGUCUGGAGCAGCAGCUGAUGAUAUAAAGCCAUGUCCACGAUGUGCUGCUUAUAUAAUAAAGAUGAAUGAUGGGAGCUGCAAUCACAUGACAUGUGCUGUUUGUGGUUGUGAGUUUUGUUGGUUGUGUAUGAAAGAAAUCUCAGAUUUGCAUUAUCUAAGUCCAUCAGGAUGUACUUUUUGGGGGAAGAAACCCUGGAGCCGAAAGAAGAAAAUAUUGUGGCAACUGGGAACACUGGUUGGUGCUCCUGUCGGAAUCGCUUUAAUAGCUGGCAUUGCUAUUCCUGCAAUGAUUAUUGGCAUUCCUGUGUAUGUGGGCCGCAAGAUUCACAAUCGCUAUGAAGGCAAGGAUGUUUCAAAGCACAAACGGAAUUUGGCCAUAGCAGGUGGUGUAACGUUGUCUGUAAUCGUGUCUCCAGUAGUAGCUGCAGUGACUGUAGGUAUCGGUGUUCCUAUUAUGUUAGCUUAUGUCUAUGGCGUAGUUCCAAUUUCUCUUUGUCGAAGCGGAGGUUGUGGAGUCUCAGCAGGCAAUGGAAAAGGAGUUAGGAUUGAAUUUGAUGAUGAAAAUGAUAUAAAUGUUGGUGGAACUAACACAGCUGUAGACACAACAUCAGUAGCAGAAGCAAGACACAACCCAAGCAUAGGGGAGGGAAGUGUUGGUGGGCUGACUGGCAGUUUGAGUGCAAGUGGAAGCCACAUGGAUCGAAUAGGAGCCAUCCGAGACAACCUGAGUGAAACGGCCAGCACCAUGGCACUAGCUGGAGCCAGUAUAACGGGGAGUCUGUCAGGAAGUGCCAUGGUAAACUGUUUUAACAGGUUGGAAGUACAAGCAGAUGUACAGAAAGAACGGUACAGUCUAAGUGGAGAAUCUGGCACAGUCAGCUUGGGAACAGUUAGUGAUAAUGCCAGCACCAAAGCAAUGGCAGGAUCCAUUCUGAAUUCCUACAUCCCAUUGGACAAAGAAGGCAACAGUAUGGAGGUGCAAGUAGAUAUUGAGUCAAAGCCAUCCAAAUUCAGGCACAACAGUGGAAGCAGUAGUGUGGAUGAUGGCAGUGCCACCCGAAGUCAUGCUGGCGGUUCAUCCAGUGGCUUGCCUGAAGGUAAAUCUAGUGCCACCAAGUGGUCCAAAGAAGCAACAGCAGGGAAAAAAUCAAAAAGUGGUAAACUGAGGAAAAAGGGUAACAUGAAGAUAAAUGAGACGAGAGAGGACAUGGAUGCACAGUUGUUAGAACAACAAAGCACGAACUCAAGUGAAUUUGAGGCUCCAUCCCUCAGUGACAGUAUGCCUUCUGUAGCAGAUUCUCACUCUAGUCAUUUUUCUGAAUUUAGUUGUUCUGACCUAGAAAGCAUGAAAACUUCUUGUAGUCAUGGUUCCAGUGAUUAUCACACCCGCUUUGCUACUGUUAACAUUCUUCCUGAGGUAGAAAAUGACCGUCUGGAAAAUUCCCCACAUCAGUGUAGCAUUUCUGUGGUUACCCAAACUGCUUCCUGUUCAGAAGUUUCACAGUUGAAUCAUAUUGCUGAAGAACAUGGUAACAAUGGAAUAAAACCUAAUGUUGAUUUAUAUUUUGGCGAUGCACUAAAAGAAACAAAUAACAACCACUCACAUCAGACAAUGGAAUUAAAAGUUGCAAUUCAGACUGAAAUUUAGGCCCAUAAAUGCUGCAGAAUAAUUACCACUGUACAACCGUGUUUGGAGCUGGUUGAACUACAUGUGACUACUUAAGUUUCAGGUUACCAGCAAAAGCCGGGUUUCAUUAUCAUAAUGCAGAUACAUUUUCUGUGUUCAGCAAGGCAUUGUGUGUCAUGUGGAUCUUAGUUACCAAACUAUGAAGUGAAGGCUUUAAAAGUGCAUUAUUUUAAGGAUAAUAAAUUUGAAGAGCAAAGCAUGUUUUGUGUGUUUGCCACAAAACAUUGCUUGAAGCACAUACUUAGAUAGAAAUUGGUCUUAAUUUAUAUAAUCAAUAUAAAAUACUAAUGCAAUUCUACAGCAUUCAAAUGAAGAAAACUUGAGGCUUUAGGGAUAAGUGGUUAGUGAUAUUUUAUUGAAACCACUAAAGAGAUAAGUUUAAAAGAACUGCAUAGGUUACUCUCAGUAUAUGAUACUCUGUAACAUUUCUAUUUAUAUCGGCAUAAAUUUCAUUUUUUUUCUUCAUAUGCAAUGUGGUUAUAUAAAGCUUAAUGCAGCUCAUUUGCUACCAUUUGGAUACUUAGACACUUUGAGCAAGAUUGUGGCAGUUUUUGCACAACUUUGAAAUAGAAAUACCUGGUACUCUAUCUUGUUUAUUGUUGAUGCCAUCUUAGAGGAAAAAAUGUAAAGGUAAGUAAUUAAGCAUAUGACAGCAACAAAUAAGAUACAUAAAACUACAAAAUAAAGUCCCAUUAGGUUAUAAGUAUUACAAAAAAUCCACCUUUCUCUAAGGGGAAGUUUGUACCCCAUUGAUUCUUGGUGCCUUUGGGAUCGACUGGGUUUUAAUGGCCUAGUUAUUUGAGGAUUUUGCUGUGUUGUUUUCCAUGUCUUCUCUGGUCACCUUGGAUUAUAUAUAAAAAUACAGGAAAUAGAUAAACAUGAAUGUGAUUAAUAAUGCUGAAAAAGUAUUAGCCUACCAAAGACACACUCAGGCUUUAGUGAAUAACUUUACAUAACCUCAGUUUUUAACACAUGCAUAUCUUCUCCAACCAUGAAAUCAAAGCACGGUGCAGAACUUGUACCAAGUACAAAAGGUCCAUGUAUGAUUAGCAUUAUUUUCUUUUGCUUUUGUUUAUGGACAAUGUUCAGCUGACAUAAGCAGAAGUUGGCCAAAAUACUGCCUGUACUGUUAAUUUCCUGUAUAAUUCACUUAAAUAAAAGCAGGUUAACCUCAAUGAUAGCAGUUAAAAUGUUCUAUCUUAUGUAUUUCUUUUAAGUAUUACCAUUAUGGUGCUACUGAGCGUUUUCUUUUGGUAAAAAGAAAAAUGCCAUGGGCUGCAGUCUUCUUCCAUCACUUUUCCCUACCAGGUCCAUUAAUAUGCUUAUAACACUAGUGCCAGUUAUUUUAUUUGAUAAUGCUUAUGGUAUUUGUAUAUUUGUUUGCAUUCCAAUUUUGUUUAAUAAUGAGUGUGUAAACUGCAUACGUUAAAUAAAUGUAAAUACUAAUGUA